UUUAUCACAUGUCUUUGUUUAAGGUUUGAGAGCUGGUAAAUAUUAGGUAUUCUUAUACAUUCUUGUCAUUAUAUUAGGAGUUACAAAGUCAAAUAUAGUUGAUCCUUGAAUGAUGUGGGGGUUAGGGACACCAACUCCCUGUACAGUCAAAAAUUCAUGUAUAAGUUUUGACUCUCUCAAAACUUUACUAAUAGCCUAUUGUUGGCCAGAAGCCUUACCAAUAACAUAAACAGUUGAUUAACACAUAUUUUGUAUGUUAUAUUUAUUAUACACUGUAUUCUUUUUUUUUUUUUUUUUUGAAACGGAGUCUCGCUCUGUCGCCCAGGCCGGACUGCGGACUGCAGUGGCGCAAUCUCGGCUCACUGCAAGCUCCGCUUCCCGGGUUCACGCCAUUCUCCUGCCUCAGCCUCCCGAGUAGCUGGGACCACAGGCGCCCGCCACCGCGCCCGGCUAAUUUUUUGUAUUUUUAGUAGAGACGGGGUUUCACCUUGUUAGCCAGGAUGGUCUCGAUCUCCUGACCUCAUGAUCCACCUGCCUCGGCCUCCCAAAGUGCUGGGAUUACAGGCGUGAGCCACCGCGCCCGGCCUACACUGUAUUCUUAUAAUAAAGUAAGCUAGAGAAAAGAAAAUGUUAUUAAGAAAAUUAUGAAGAAGAGAAAUAUAUAUGCUAUUCAUUAAGUGGAAGUAGAUCAUCAUGAAGGUUUUCAUUCUUGUCAUCUUCAUGUUUAGUAGGCUAAGGAGGAAGAGGAAGAGGAGGGAUUGGUUUUACUGUCUCAGGGGUUGCAGAAGCAGAGGAAGGGGAAGCAGGAGAGCAAGCACACUCAAUAUAGCCUUUAGAGAAAAAAAAUCUGUGUAUAAGUGGACCUGUGCAGUUCAAAUUUAUGUUGUUCAAGGGUCAACUGUAGCUUCAAAAGUCAGGAAACUAAUGUAAAUAAGUCAGAUAUAAGGCAAUAGAGAAUUUUAAAGUCUGCAUAACCCAAAGGAAGUCAUUCUCACUCAAAGACAAAACAUAGUCUUGGGAAAACCAAACAUUCUAAAUCCAGACAAAUUAUAUUUUCAUCCUGAGUGAUUGCAUGUGCCCCCUCAAUAACUGUCUAUGCCAAUGAGUUACAGGUUUAUAUUCCUAGCCCAAGUCACUCCUCUGAGCUCACACCCAUAUUUCCUGUUGCCUAUUUUUAACCCAUCUGUAUCUUUAAAAUGGUUUUCUUGUAGACAGCAUAUAUAGUAGGCUAAUAAUUUUUAAUAAAAUCUGAAAAUCUCUGCCUUUCAAUUGGAAUAUUUAACCCAUUUAUGUUUAAUAUAAUUAUCAUUAUGGUUAGGCCAUCUAUUAUCUAGCUGUUGCUUUCUAUAUGGCCCAUUGGCUCUUCGUUCUAUUUUUCUCUCCCUACUUUUAGAUUAACGGAGUGUUUUUUGUGAUUCCAUCUUAUCUAUAUUAUUGGCUUAACAGACAUACUUUUUCAUGGUUGUUUUAGUCUGUAAUAGUCCAUCUCAAGCAAUCUGGCUUCAGAACACUGGCACUUACUCACCACACCCCUCUGUGCUAAGCUAUAUGGAGAAUGCAGAAAUGAAAGAGACACCAGAAAAUGAAGUUAAAAAAAACUUAACAUUCAGUAGAGGGAGGUGGGUCAUGUUCAUGAACAACAAUAAUAUGAGAUAAAAAUGGUGUGAAAUUCAUAAUUUAAAAGAACCAAAGUGCUUUGGUUCUUUAAGGGGGGAAGAUGAACUUCAGUAGCUAGAUUGAUAACAGAGGUGGGAUGUGUGAAAGAGAAUUAGGGAAGAUAUUAUGGAGAAAGUGGGAACUCACCCCUGCUAAGAGUAGUUGAGUAUGGUGAAGACAUAUGGGAAGAUUUGUACUUAUCAAGUUGGUUCAUGUGAUAUUUCCUCAUAGUUAUCUUACAUAUAAUUUUUUGAUAAAUCAACAAUUUGAUGCAAGUCAUUUUAAAAGAGCACACAUACACACAAAUAAUGCAUGUGUCUUCAUAUAUCAUUUUUUAAAGAAUACACAGGAUAUAACUCUUCAUUUCUUAAUGAAAUUUCUAGCCUAUUUCAUGGUUCACAUUUUGACUAUAACCUUUGAGGUUAGUUAGUUUUUUUUUUUUUUUUUAAGACAGAGUCUCACUCUGUCACCCAGGUUGGAGUGCAGUGGCAUGAUCUCGGCUCACUGCAACUUCUGCCUCGUGGGUUCAAGCAAUUCUCUUGCCUCAGCCUCCUGAGUAGCUGGGACUACAGGUGUAUGCUGCAACGCCUGGCUAAUUUUUUGUGUUUUAGCAGAGAUGGGGUUUUACUGUGUUGGAAAUUUUUUGUUUGUUUGUUUGUUUUGAGACGGAGUUUUGCUCUGUCACCCAAGCUGGAGUGCAGUGGCGCAAUCUUGGCUCACUGCAACCUCCGCCUCCCGGGUUCAAGAAAUUCUCCUGCCUCAGCCUCCUGAGUAGCUGGGACUAUAGGCACGCACCACUACACCUGGCUAAUUUUUUGUAUUUUUAGUAGAGAUGGGGUUUCACCAUGUUAGCCAAGAUGGUCUCGAUCUGACCUCGUGAUCUGCCUGCCUUGGCUUCUCAAAGUCCUGGGAUUACAGGCAUGAGCCACCAUGCCUGGCCCCAGAUUUUUAACAAACACAUAGGAUCCAUCCACACUGAUGAGUAAUAUCACAUUAAAGUGGCUAACUUGGGAUGUUCCUGGAGUUUACUGAUUCCUGUGAGGUUGCCGUUGUUCAAGGUACUUUGGGGUCUCUUCUUAUAGAAUUGUCUUCUGAAGGUCAGUGUACAAGGUAGUCUUAUGACUUAAUGGCUUCACAGCUUUGGAAACAAAUGCUACUUCUCAAGCCUAAUCAAAAAUCUUAUCAACCAGACAUGCUUUCUAAGAGUGGCUUUCAUAUAUUUCAAAACAUGAGACAUCUCAUUAUGUCUUUUCAAAGGACAUAGAGCUCAAUUCUCAAAGGAUAGAGAACAUUCUGAGGAACGGGCUAUGAGCUCCAGAGGUAAUUCUAAGAGAGGAAAUUUCAACAAUCAUUUGAGCAAUGGCAUCUUUGGAGUAAAUGUGUGGUUUUUCCUUGUUAUCUGAUUUUUCAGGGAAAUGGUACUCAUUUAGAUGCAUGAGUUCCUACAUAUUGGCCUUAAAGGUCUUCAUUAUAGUCACACUUCAUAGAGGAAUAAAUGGUAGAGUAGAAAGAAUAUUGGCUUUGGAGAAAGACACCUUACUAUCCUACCACCUUACCCUACCAUGUACUAACAGUUUGACAUGAGGCAAAUGACUUAACUUCUCAAAUCUUUCCUUUUCUGUAUAACAUGGCCAAUGACACCAGAGCUGUUGGGAAGACAGAAAGAGAUAUGUGUAAAGCAUCAGGUAUAGAACCUAGCUCACAGGGAGUACACAAUGAAUGCUAGCCCUCUACUUCCUUUCUUUCCUGUGGAAGUUCCCCUCUGAGACUUCAUAUUUAUUUCUUAGAGGAGAAAUUGUCAAUAAGAGUCAGGCUGGCCUUGAAACUACCAUUUCUAAUCCUUCCAGACUCCAUCUACUCCAAUAUCAAGUCCUGUUGGUAAAACCUGAGCAGAAGUAGAAGUGAUUGCAUCUCCCCGAGAGUGAGCUGCUCAGCUUUUGGGGGAUGAGCUGACUGGUCUUUUUCUGUGAUGUUCAGCUAGUCAAUUUAGGGGAUUUACAUGACUAAACAAAAAGUCUCCUUUUGAUUCCAUUGCAGUUAAUGCUUGAAUGUGCUUUCACCUUUUGUGAUGUUAUGUGCCAGUUCAUUAACUGGACACCUUCACCAGUCAGGGUCUUGGCAAAACACAGAGGUUAUCCUGAAAUUGGGUGGAUUGGAGAGUUUAAUAAUGAUGGGAUCAUUCACAAAGGGUGUGGGCAAGGAAAAGCAGCUAUGGCAGCAACAUGGUUGGCAAUACUACUAGACCUGAAGAGGCAAAGGAAUGAAGGAGUGACCAGACCUGGAGACGUAGUUGAGGCCUGUUUGUAGCAGCUGUGGCUAUCUGUGGAAGCAGCCAUUGCUAACCCAGCUAGAAGAAAGCCAGGGGAUAAAUUCCCUCAUUUCACUCUUCUCUGACUCGAAUCUUCUGCCAGUACUAUCUGUUGGCCAAAUCUUACCAGAAGCCACAGGGCAGGGACCACAGAGCCCAACUUUUCAUGGCACAGGGCAGAGUGGAGACGAAUGCUGUGUAGAUAUGGUGGAGGAGAGAAUAUUCAGCAACCCUUCCAAAUUGUGCACUCAGAUCAAAUAAUGUUUCCAUUUCUGUUGUUCUACUCGUAGGAAGAAGUUUUCAUGUCAAUGGGUGACGUGUGACUUAAUUUACUUCUUUACCAAUAUUAUAAACUAUUUUUAUGUUAACAAAUGCUAAACAGCUUGUUUUCUUAUUUUUACUGGUAAUAUCUAUUAACUUAUACCUGUCAUUCUGAGUAAUUGUAUGUACUGGGCAUAGCAUAAUAGAAAGAUUGGGAUGGAUUUGGGAAGGCUGUAGAAAAAGGAAAAGGGCUGGUUGAAGCAUUUUGUAUUUUGUGAUUUUGACACAACAUUUUGUAUUUAAGAAAAAAAGAAAACAUUCUGAUGAUUAAAGUCUAUGAAAUCGAAGUUUCUGUCUCCUGAAAAGACUACCCCUAUUCAUCUGUGCAUUUUCGCCACAAGAGUGAUAAUCAAGUGAAUAAUCGGCAGUCUGAAGUGCUCAUCAACAGCAAACUGCAGAAUGAAAAAUGGAUGAAUGUCAAAGUGGGAGACAUCAUUAAAUUAGAAAAUAACCAAUUUGUUGCUGGAUUGUUGUCUGUGAGGUGCCUAACAACAAGUUAGAUAAAUUCAUGGGAAUCCUUUCUUGGAAAGACAGCAAGCAUUCCCUCAACAAUGAGAAGAUAAUCCUGAGAGGCUGCAUCCUGAGAAAUACCAGCUGGUGUUUUGGAAUGGUUAUUUUUGCAGGUCCUGACACUAAACUAAUGCAGAAUAGUGGUAAGACAAAGUUUAAAAGGACAAGCAUUGAUAGAUUGAUGAAUACUCUAGUACUAUGGAUUUUUGGGUUUCUGAUAUGCUUGGGAAUUAUUCUUGCAAUAGGAAAUUCAAUCUGGGAGAGUCAAACUGGGGACCAAUUCAGAACUUUCCUCUUUUGGAAUGAAGGAGAGAAGAGCUCUGUGUUCUCCGGAUUCUUAACAUUCUGGUCAUAUAUUAUUAUUCUCAAUACAGUUGUACCCAUUUCCUUAUAUGUGAGUGUGGAAGUAAUUCGUCUAGGACACAGUUAUUUUAUAAACUGGGACCGGAAGAUGUAUUAUUCUCGAAAAGCAAUACCUGCAGUGGCUCGAACGACCACGCUCAAUGAGGAACUGGGGCAGAUUGAGUACAUUUUCUCCGACAAAACGGGUACCCUCACUCAAAACAUCAUGACCUUUAAAAGAUGUUCCAUUAAUGGGAGAAUCUAUGGUGAAGUACAUGAUGACCUGGAUCAGAAGACAGAAAUAACUCAGGAAAAAGAGCCUGUGGAUUUCUCAGUCAAAUCUCAAGCGGAUAGAGAAUUUCAGUUCUUUGACCACCAUCUGAUGGAAUCCAUUAAAAUGGGUGAUCCCAAAGUUCAUGAAUUCCUUAGGUUACUUGCUCUCUGCCACACUGUAAUGUCAGAAGAGAAUAGCGCAGGAGAGCUGAUUUACCAAGUUCAGUCACCUGAUGAAGGGGCUCUAGUGACUGCCGCUAGAAAUUUUGGGUUCAUUUUUAAAUCCCGGACCCCAGAGACCAUAACAAUAGAAGAAUUGGGAACACUAGUUACUUAUCAAUUACUUGCCUUUUUGGAUUUCAACAACACCAGAAAAAGGAUGUCUGUCAUAGUUCGAAACCCAGAAGGACAGAUAAAGCUUUAUUCCAAAGGAGCAGAUACUAUUCUGUUUGAAAAACUUCAUCCUUCCAAUGAAGUCCUUUUGUCUUUGACGUCAGACCACCUCAGUGAAUUUGCAGGGGAAGGCCUUCGGACCUUGGCCAUCGCAUACAGAGACCUGGAUGACAAGUACUUUAAAGAGUGGCAUAAGAUGCUUGAAGAUGCGAAUGCUGCCACAGAAGAGAGGGAUGAACGAAUAGCUGGGCUAUAUGAAGAAAUUGAAAGAGAUUUGAUGCUACUAGGUGCCACUGCUGUAGAAGAUAAGUUACAGGAGGGUGUUAUUGAAACAGUUACAAGUUUAUCACUAGCCAAUAUUAAGAUCUGGGUCCUAACAGGAGACAAACAAGAAACUGCCAUCAACAUCGGUUAUGCCUGCAACAUGCUGACUGACGACAUGAAUGAUGUGUUUGUGAUAGCAGGGAAUAAUGCUGUGGAAGUGAGAGAAGAACUCAGGAAAGCAAAACAAAAUUUGUUUGGACAAAACAGAAAUUUUUCCAAUGGCCAUGUAGUUUGUGAAAAAAAGCAGCAGCUGGAGUUGGAUUCUAUUGUAGAAGAAACCAUAACAGGAGAUUAUGCCUUAAUCAUAAAUGGCCACAGUUUGGCUCAUGCCCUAGAAAGUGAUGUCAAGAAUGAUCUCCUAGAACUUGCUUGCAUGUGUAAGACUGUAAUUUGCUGCAGGGUCACUCCACUCCAGAAAGCCCAAGUGGUAGAGCUGGUGAAGAAGUACAGAAAUGCUGUUACUUUGGCCAUUGGUGAUGGAGCCAAUGAUGUCAGCAUGAUUAAAAGUGCUCACAUUGGUGUUGGCAUCAGCGGCCAGGAAGGAUUGCAAGCAGUCUUAGCCAGCGACUAUUCAUUUGCACAGUUUAGAUAUCUCCAAAGGCUUCUCCUUGUUCAUGGAAGGUGGUCUUAUUUCCGAAUGUGCAAAUUCUUAUGCUAUUUCUUCUAUAAGAAUUUUGCAUUUACACUUGUGCAUUUCUGGUUUGGUUUCUUCUGUGGUUUCUCAGCCCAGACUGUUUAUGACCAGUGGUUCAUCACCCUUUUUAACAUUGUUUACACAUCACUGCCUGUUUUAGCCAUGGGGAUUUUUGACCAGGAUGUGAGUGACCAGAACAGCGUGGACUGUCCCCAGCUCUACAAACCAGGACAGCUGAAUCUGCUUUUUAACAAGCGUAAAUUUUUCAUUUGCGUGUUGCAUGGAAUCUACACCUCAUUAGUCCUUUUCUUCAUCCCCUAUGGGGCCUUUUACAACGUGGCUGGAGAAGAUGGGCAACAUAUUGCUGACUACCAGUCCUUUGCAGUUACCAUGGCCACAUCUUUGGUCAUUGUGGUCAGUGUGCAGAUAGCCUUGGAUACCAGUUACUGGACUUUCAUUAAUCACGUCUUCAUCUGGGGGAGCAUUGCCAUUUAUUUCUCCAUUUUAUUUACAAUGCACAGUAAUGGCAUCUUUGGCAUCUUCCCAAACCAGUUUCCAUUUGUUGGUAAUGCACGACAUUCCCUGACCCAGAAGUGCAUCUGGCUUGUAAUUCUCUUAACAACAGUGGCUUCAGUUAUGCCAGUGGUGGCAUUCAGAUUUUUGAAGGUGGAUUUAUACCCAACCCUGAGUGAUCAGAUCCGCCGGUGGCAGAAGGCUCAAAAGAAGGCAAGGCCUCCAAGUAGCCGAAGGCCUCGGACCCGCAGGUCAAGCUCAAGAAGGUCUGGAUAUGCUUUUGCUCACCAAGAAGGCUAUGGAGAGCUUAUCACAUCUGGAAAAAAUAUGCGAGCUAAAAAUCCACCCCCAACAUCAGGGCUGGAAAAGACACAUUAUAAUAGCACUAGCUGGAUUGAAAAUUUAUGUAAGAAAACCACAGACACCGUGAGCAGCUUUAGCCAGGAUAAAACAGUGAAACUGUGAGUCAAUAUGAAUUUAAACCACGUAGUUAUCUUUUCACUUCAGGUGGAGCUGAAAUUCUGCUGGCUCCAGAGUUUGAGAUUUGAGGCAAGAGGUGGGGCAGGCAGAUUGCCUCACUUAACUUAAAUCUGCGGCAGACAACUGCCAGUGCCCAUCAAACAGGAGUGUGCGCUAUGGAAAACCAGGCCAGAGGGUCACUGUCUGGUUUGUGAUUUGGUGGACAAAACACUCGCUGUUACAAGUACAGAUUUUUUUUUUUUUUAAAUCAACCUAGAUACCAAUUGACCUGAACUUUAGAAUCUUAUUUAUGGAGAAAAACUUGUAAAGCUGCAUAUUCACUGAAUGGAUCCUCAGGCGGAUAAAAGGGUGCAUUUUAAAGGUAUAUAUCCAAGCUGAAAAGCAUGCCUAUUGACAGAUAAACAUGUAUCUGUAAGAUCAGCCUUUCCCAAGGUAUACUUUUAAAAUUUAAAGCGUGUACUGUGUUGCUUUCAGACUGAGUUGCAUGUCACUCUUUAGUCUUGAUAUCUACCUGUCUGUUCAGCCAGGACAACAAAUGGCUUCCAAGCCUGAAGAAUACAAAAGUGUGCUUGUGUUUCUCAUUUUUAUACCAGUCUAGGGACAAAGGAGACUGAACAUCUUUGCAGCAGGAUAGGCUGGUAAUUUGAUCAAAUUUAUUCAAAAAGCUCUCAGUCUGUGUCAUGUAAGGACAUGCUUAUGAAAUGUGAGAGAGGCUCGCCACUAAGUAUUCUAAAUACUUUUCAAUGGCUUUUCUAACAACCUCAGUAGUAAUUUGCUGAGCAUCAUCCAGACCAUUAAUAGAAUCAGCAAAGCACUGGAAUUUCACACUUUAAUGAUAAUAUUCCACAUAGUCUAUGGGCAAAUAUUUUCAACAUUUCCAAUUUUUAAAGCUUCAGAAUUGAAGCCAAACAAAUUAAUAAAUAAUUGUUUUAAUUACUAUUUAAAAACUCAGGUUUAGAUUGUUUAAAAUUAGUUGCUUUUGAUACUCAGCUGUCAUGUUUAUAAUUCAAACAUGUAGUAAACAUAUGUAGGUAAGGUUGUUUUUUUGGAGAUGUUGCAGCUCAAAUUUCAGUCCACAUAUGAAUCAUCAGUGUAUUUUCCAUAAAGUGAUUCGGGCAUAUUUGUGUGAAAACCUCAGUUCUGUCACUUCUUACCUCUAUAAACUUGGACGAUAAUGUGCCUUCUCUGAGACUCAGUUUCUUCCUCUGUAAAAUGAGGACAUACUACCUACCUCAUGUGGUUGGUUGAUGAUUGUCUGUCAAAGCACAAACUCUGAAAUUAUUAAAAACAUAAUUAUUUCAUAAACAGAUGAGUUAAGUUCCAGUUAACUCAACAUCAGUAUAACAGAGCAAUUGGAAGAGAAUAUGAAAAAACUGGAAUCUAAAUAGUCAGUGAGGAAGGCUUUGAUAAAAUGAAAUUGCCAGAAAGAUAUAAAACUGGUUAGGGUCCUACAGGGAAAUAAAAUUAUAACCGUGGAGGUACAUUUCUCUACCAGAAAGCAAAAAUAAAGCAUCAUGUCUUAAUGGUUUUCUACAAAUCAACUUCUAAUUCUACAGAGUCCUUAAUCUGGUCCCUAUUAAAUUCUUGGUCAGACAAAGUUACAUUUCCCAAGAGAGUCAGGUGACACUUGAGUGAGUUUGAUGGAUAAUGAGCUAAUGUGAUAUCUAUAGGUCACAAUUUUUUAAAACCAAAAUUUUCAAGUCUGGGAUAAUCUUUCCUAAAUGGGAUCAAAUGAAAUAAUAUGUGUAAAAGAGUCAAAUGCAGUCCUUUACCAUAGUAACUGCCUAUGGACGUUGUCUUUCCCUUACAUGCCUGCCUACACUUAACCAGAUGUUGGUUUUCAAUGUCUAAUUUGUCAUUAGUUUCACCACAUUUGCUCACUUUUUGUAACAUUUUUGCAAGAUUUGAAAACUUUCAGUAAAUGUUUUGGCACUAUUGGUA